GCACCGGGAGGAAGCUGCCUUGGAAGAGGUGGGGGCGGCGACGGGAGGGGCGGCGAGCCCCCGGGAGCCUGGGCGUUAGGCCCGGGCGUGGCGGGGCCCCGGCGGCCUGGGGGGUCUCCUGGGCCCCCCCCCACCCAUGGAGCCCGCCGCCCCGGAGGUCGGUCUCAGAUGACUGAACUGGGCACCGAGCGCCCCUGGUGUCCCUCGCAGUGGACUGACGCCGCAGGGGCGAGCUAGCCGGCUCCGCGCCUCUCCGCGGGAUCCAGACGCCUCCUGGGGCUGCUGGCGGAGGGUCUGAGGCGGCGCGGCCAUGGCUCACCUCCGGGGAUUUGCCAACCAGCACUCUCGAGUGGACCCUGAGGAGCUCUUCACCAAGCUCGACCGCAUUGGCAAGGGCUCGUUUGGGGAGGUCUACAAGGGCAUCGAUAACCACACAAAGGAGGUGGUGGCCAUCAAGAUCAUCGACCUGGAGGAGGCCGAGGAUGAGAUCGAGGACAUCCAGCAGGAGAUCACUGUCCUCAGUCAGUGCGACAGCCCCUACAUCACCCGCUACUUUGGCUCCUACCUAAAGAGCACCAAGCUAUGGAUCAUCAUGGAGUACCUGGGCGGCGGCUCAGCACUGGACUUGCUUAAACCAGGUCCCCUGGAGGAGACAUACAUUGCCACGAUCCUGCGGGAGAUUCUGAAGGGCCUGGAUUAUCUGCACUCCGAACGCAAGAUCCACCGAGACAUCAAAGCUGCCAACGUGCUACUCUCGGAGCAGGGUGACGUGAAGCUGGCGGACUUUGGGGUAGCAGGGCAGCUCACAGACACGCAGAUUAAGAGGAACACAUUCGUGGGCACCCCCUUCUGGAUGGCACCUGAGGUCAUCAAGCAGUCGGCCUACGACUUCAAGGCUGACAUCUGGUCCCUGGGGAUCACAGCCAUCGAGCUGGCCAAGGGGGAGCCUCCAAACUCUGACCUCCACCCCAUGCGCGUCCUGUUCCUGAUUCCCAAGAACAGCCCACCCACACUGGAGGGCCAGCACAGCAAGCCCUUCAAGGAGUUCGUGGAGGCCUGCCUCAACAAAGACCCCCGAUUCCGGCCCACGGCCAAGGAGCUCCUGAAGCACAAGUUCAUCACACGCUACACCAAGAAGACCUCCUUCCUCACGGAGCUCAUCGACCGCUAUAAGCGCUGGAAGUCAGAGGGGCAUGGCGAGGAGUCCAGCUCUGAGGACUCUGACAUUGAUGGCGAGGCGGAGGACGGGGAGCAGGGCCCCAUCUGGACGUUCCCCCCUACCAUCCGGCCGAGUCCACACAGCAAGCUUCACAAGGGGACGGCCCUGCACAGUUCACAGAAGCCUGCGGAGCCCGUCAAGAGGCAGCCGAGGUCCCAGUGCCUGUCCACGCUGGUCCGGCCCGUCUUCGGAGAGCUCAAAGAGAAGCACAAGCAGAGCGGCGGGAGCGUGGGUGCGCUGGAGGAGCUGGAGAACGCCUUCAGCCUGGCCGAGGAGUCCUGCCCCGGCAUCUCAGACAAGCUGAUGGUGCACCUGGUGGAGCGAGUGCAGAGGUUUUCACACAACAGAAACCACCUGACAUCCACCCGCUGAAGCGCACUGCUGUUCAGAUAGGGGACGGAAGGUCGUUUGUUUUUGUUCUGAGCUCCAUAAGAACUGUGCUGACUUGGAAGGUGCCCUGUGCUAUGUCGUGCCUGCAGGGACACGUCGGAUCCCGUGGGCCUCACAUGCCAGGUCACCAGGUCACCGUCUCCUUCCACCCCUGCAGUGUGCUGUUGUGCACGUCAGGGACGCUGUUCUCUAUGCCCACUGCCCUCCUCCCUCUCCUGGCCCAGCAGUAUUGCUCACGGGGGCUCCAGCCGCCGGCGUGGCCCUCAUGAGCUACGCCUGGGUCUUCUGCAGACUCAUGCAGCCCUAUGGCCGCUCAGACCAAGGCGCAGAGCAACUAUCAGGGCAGCUCUGCCUCCUCCUCCCAUGAGGUGGGGAGAGGCAACAGGGCAGCCCCCAGAGGAGUGUCCUGGCCGCUGUCCUCCCGGGGCCCAUGAUGGCCAUAGAUUUGCCUUGUGGUGUUGGAUCAGGUACUGUGUCUGCUCAUAAGUACUUGUGUCAUCCAGAAUGUUUUGUUUUUUAAGAAAAUUGAAUUACUUGUUUCCUGAAAUAUUCUGAGGUUAAUAUGUUAGUUUUCAUAGAACAUUGAGAGGCCCCUGCCACUUUCAAUAAAGACCUGACUUGGAGACAUGCAGGUGUGUGUGGUGGGGCCCGGGCCAUGCGGGGCUGCAGCGUCCCUGGUCCCGAGUCCUCAUCACAGCACGCAGAGACGGCAGCCCAGCCCCCCUUCGAAACUUCCCUGUGACGGAUUCCUGGGCUCUGCUUGGCCCACCGGAAGAACAGAGCAGGCAGAGGAGAAUGCAGGUGGGGAGAUGCUGUUUGUUUAUUUUUAAUCAAAUGUGUGUGAACAAAGCAGUCGCCCAUCUACUUCCCGUUGGAAGGAAUGCUGGGCAGUAAUAAAUUAGACGGCCCCACCCUCCCAGGGCACAGGGGGACUUUGGUUUCUGCUUCUCUAGAGGUACAUGGGGAACAAGCGUGGCUUCUGCCAGACUUGUUUAGCUGUGACCUGCAGGGCAGGCCCCUGGGGCUGCCACUUGGUUCACCAGAUGGAAGGUCAGCAUGGCUGUGCCACGCUUGUCUGAGAGGGUCCUGGCAGUGGGUACGCAGGGUGUAUGGCAGGGCCUCUUUUCCAGUGCUUGCUCUAGGCCAGUCCUCGGCAGGGACCCUGCUCUGGGGAGAGAGGCAGGGUGUGCCCAGGCUUUGGUCCGAUGCCGAGAGCACUGCUCAGGCCUUGUCUGCGUCUUUGAGCCAGGGGCCUGGGAGCUGUGGCUUGAGCGGCUCCGCGCUCAAGACUCGCACAUUUUUCCCAGGGCCCCAGAUAGCUGCUGGCAUGCACUAGGUCCUGGGUGGGGGGAUGAAGCCCCUCCCAGAUGUUACAUGAGGCCCACCCACACUGCUGGUGCCAGUGGGGAUCCAGUGAGACCACAGCCACUUCCCAUCUGUUGAGAAGCCUCAGGACAGAGGUCACCUCUGUGUCCUGCUGUUCUUUGUAGUUGUGUCCAAACCUGGGCAGGUUGAGCGUCAUUCCUCCUUCCCCCUGACCAUCCCCUCCAGCCCUGAGGAGGGUUGGGGGCCAUCCUGCACGAUGCUUGGGGCCCUCCCGGCUGAGCUGCUGGCCCCCUGGAUCACCUCCAUCCACCUGGAGGAGAGGGCGGCCAUCAGACCAGUGAGCCAUCUUGUGCUCAGACACUGUCCCAAGAACAACCCAGGAUAUGGGACAAGCAGGACAAAAGAAGGGUUAAAAACCUGGGGCCGGGUGCGGUGGCUCAUGCCUAUAAUCCCAGCACUUUGGGAGGCUGAGGCAGAUGGAUCACUUGAGGUCAGGAGUUCGAGACCAGCCUGGCCAACAUGGUGAAACCCUGUCUCUACUAAAAAUACAAAAAUUAGCCAGGCGGCGUGGCGUGCAUGCCUGUAAUCUCAGUUACUCAGGAGGCUGAGGCAGAAGAAUCGCUUGAACCCUGGAGGUGCAGGUUAUAGUGAGCCAAGAUUGUAUCACUGCACUCCAGCCUGAGUGACAGAGGGAGACGCCAUCUCCAAAAAAAAAAAAAACAAAGCAUUGCUGUUUUUUGGAAAUGCUGGAAGCAUUGCUCAGCCCUUCCUUUCCAGGGCCCAGAAAACUUGCCUCCACCACCAUGAGUAGAAAUGGGAGCUGAGCGGACAUCGAAAUGGGCAGCUGACCAGGGCUGCCUCCUGCAAAAUUACCUUUCAAAUGUGUACUUGCUCUCAGCCCGGAAGAAGUAGACGUGGGAUUUGAACUGGAGCUUGAAAACAUAGUCUUUGUGUAUGCCAUCGGCCUCCCUGGGGAUGCUCACGCUGUAGCCCAGCAGCGGGAGGCUGGCCAGUGGGUAGUCAUCCUGCAAGACAGCAUAGGGACACGGGUUCCAGGGGCUGGGUUGCCACAGGGAAUGCCCAUUCCUCUGCUACCUGCACAACGGUGGCACGUACAAAUGCCCACGGGCCAAGGGAGCCAGUUUCCCUGUUCACACAGCACAGGGUGUGUGGGCAAAGCAUGGGAGGGCAGAACCAAAAUACAAAAGGGACACAGGUGAGCAGGGUUAAGUGUCUGUCUGCUAGCAUCACCUGCAUUGGGCUCCAGUGAAACUCCAGUACCUGAUGAGUUUUGUAGAAGAACAAACAGAAGUUGGUAAAGACGACCCAGAGCUUCUGCCAGCCAUGACUGUUUUUGAACUUUCUUAGCAGAUAUCCUGAAAGCUGGUUCUGUCAAUAAAGGAAAAAUGCAGGUGCAUUAACCAGCACCCAGGACCCCUUGUGGGAGUGGGUUUGCUCCCCAAGACUAAGCCUCUGCAUGCUUUCUCCAGCUGAGGCCUUGGUUUUACCUCUGGACUGCUAUGAACAGCAGCUUUAUCAGUACUUAAGUCCAACAGAAGCAUGUUAAAAACCUAGAGUGACAUUCCAGGCACCAAGUAAAGUGAGUUCCCUUUCCCUGUGCACAAUAAAGUCAGUGUUCAGUAACCAA